AAGGAGAGUCCGGUUUAACCGUCACCGGGAAGCGCGCUCGUUCGGGAUCGCCGAGGGGGCUGAGGUAAAGACUGGGUCAUUACCUCAGGACAGGCGGUCGCUGUCCCGGGUUCUCGUACGGGUGACACCUGCAACCUUGAUGUCUGGCGGGCGGCAAGGGGCUCCGCGGGAGAGUGGAGAGGCGCCGCAGGAAGCCCAGCCACCUUCAGGCCACCGCCGACCCCACUGUGCGUCUGGGAGGCGCUGGGCGCGCACCGGUCAGCGGAGGCGGGAGAGUCUGUGAUCCCAGGGAGCUGCGGGUCUCGCCGCCUGCAGUGCGGAAGACCCGUGACCGGCGCAGACCCCGGCCUUACCUUCCGAGGGUCGAACUGUGCCUGGUAUUUGCCUCUUUCCUCCCGCCCACGGGGUUGCUCAGAGUCGGGCCACCUCACCUGAGGUUUUCCAGAGUGAGAAUGAACUGAGCGUCCUGGGAGCAACUCCGCAUCAGGGUAGAGGCGAAGACGCUCCUAAUGAGCACAGCACGUUUUUUUGUUUGUUUGUUUGCUUGUUUUGUUUUUUUAACGCUUGGGUAGCGCUCACAUCUUCGGACGUCAGUGGUUGUGUUGAUAUGUAUUGAUAUGCGACCUCCCCCCAGCCAGGCGGCCUCAGUACUGUCAAGAUGAUAAGCAUGGAAUAAAGCUUCAGAAGGGUCUUUACCAAUCUUUCUCCUACCAACUUUUACAUACAUGAAAUCAGGUUAAAAUGAACUUUACAGAAAUACUUCACAAGGGAAUAAAGUAGAGGAAAAAGGGAUAACAUGUAACAUGGAGUCAAGGAAAAAGAGUGUGAAGUAGUUUUGCUCUCUCUAUCUUGCAAAUAGGAGUCCUUAAAGACAACUGGGAGAAGGGGUUUGAGAUAGUGAAUUCCUAAGAAGAAAAUAAUGGAUUGCAUAUUAGUUGUUCUCUAAGUGGACUCAACAGUGUGCAAGCUUGUUGGAAAAGCCAAAAGAAGAUGGCAACUCCUUAUGUCCCAGUUCCUAUGCCCAUAGGAAACUCUGCUUCCAGUUUUACAACAAACAGAAAUCAAAGAAGUUCUUCUUUUGGCAGUGUCUCAACAAGCUCAAAUUCUUCUAAGGGCCAGUUAGAAGACUCAAAUAUGGGUAAUUUUAAACAGACAAGUGUUCCUGAUCAAAUGGAUAAUACUUCAUCUGUCUGUAGCAGUCCCCUCAUUAGGACUAAAUUUACAGGUACAGCUUCUUCCAUUGAGUAUUCUACUAGACCAAGAGACACUGAAGAACAAAAUCCGGAAACAGUGAAUUGGGAAGAUAGACCAUCUACACCUACUAUACUGGGUUAUGAAGUGAUGGAAGAAAGAGCUAAAUUUACUGUAUAUAAAAUACUAGUAAAGAAAACCCCAGAAGAAAGCUGGGUAGUUUUCAGAAGAUACACUGACUUCUCUAGGCUUAAUGACAAAUUAAAAGAGAUGUUUCCAGGUUUUCGACUAGCACUUCCUCCAAAACGCUGGUUUAAAGAUAAUUACAAUGCUGACUUUUUAGAAGACAGACAAUUAGGAUUACAAGCGUUUCUUCAAAAUUUAGUAGCUCACAAGGACAUUGCUAACUGCCUUGCAGUGAGAGAAUUUCUUUGUUUGGAUGAUCCACCGGGUCCAUUUGAUAGCCUAGAAGAAAGCAGGGCAUUCUGUGAAACUUUAGAAGAGACAAACUACCGCUUACAGAAAGAACUACUUGAAAAACAAAAGGAGAUGGAAUCACUAAAGAAACUGCUCAGUGAGAAGCAACUUCAUAUAGACACUUUAGAGAACAGAAUCAGAACAUUGUCUUUAGAACCUGAAGAAUCACUGGAUGUGUCAGAAACAGAAGGUGAACAGAUCCUAAAGGUGGAGUCCUCUGCACUUGAGGUUGAUCAAGAUGUCCUGGAUGAAGAAUCUAGAGCUGAUAAUAAACCAUGCUUAAGUUUUAGUGAACCUGAAAAUGCUGUAUCAGAGAUAGAAGUAGCAGAAGUGGCAUAUGAUGCUGAAGAAGACUAAUGUAUCACAAGCAGUUCCCUCCAUUUAGACUAUUCAAAAAUUUAGAAGAGUGGCAAAUACUAUUUUAAAAGAAGAACCAAGAACUGUAAAACAUAUAGAAAAGAGCAAGAAUGCACAUGUAUAAAGUUUACAUAAAGAAGUUUUUUUAAGUUAUUGAGAUAGGAAAUAUAUUCACUGCUGCUUUUAAUUGUAUUUUAUCCAAUUACAUUUAAUACACUAAAAAAAAUCUUGUUGGAAUUCUGUUAUCAAGGCCCACAUUCUUAAAUACUGUGCAUAAAUUAUUAUGGUGUUUUGCCUAUAUAUUGCUCCAAACUACUGUGUAUAUAUGUAUGUGUGUUAAAUCACCAAUUAUAUUAAUCAAAUGGAAAUUAAUUGCAUGUUACUAUCUGGGUGAUAUAUUCUUCUUUAUAUCUCUGACAUGACAUAUUUUCAUUAAUAGUUUAAAUCAGUGACCAUCAUAAUAAAGAUAAAAUUUAGUUGAGUUUUUAAUGUUUACAUGUUUACAUCUCUAAAUAAAAUUUGCUUAUUUGAAAUGUUAAUGCUCUUUAGAAAAAUGACUUUCUAGUACCAAAGGAAAACUACUUGAAAGAGCUGUAAUCAUAUAGCUAAAGUGAUAAGAUAGCCUUGAUUUUAAAAGCUGAUUCAUUAAUAUCAAAAUACUUUAAUAAGUGUCACAGUUAUUAAUAUGUUACAUUUGUUUAGUUUCCACGUAAUCUUUAUCUCUACCUAGAUUUAGUGAGUUUGCCUCUUUCAGAAUACUACCUCCUUUUGUUAAGGCAUAUUCUUUCGAAAAUAUAGAUUCUAAAUAAAUAGGGGCUUAUACAAAAAAGAAAAUAAAAAGCCAUAUAUACUGCAAAGUUCCUAACUGGCUUGACUCCUGACAUUGCAUUUUUAUUUCUAUUUGUGUGAAGAUGUUGUUAUACUGUAUUAUGGCUGAUUUUCUUUUUAAUAUAUUUAGCCAAGUGAUGCACUUUAUGAUAAUUAAACUCUUUUGUGCCAAGUUUAAUUGGUGGAUUUUUUUAGUAAGUAGAGUUAGGAGAAAGAAUUAUGUAGUGCCUUUACUAUUUCACUUUCUACAAAAGUCUCCUAGGGUCUUUGAGUCAGCUUUAUGAAAAAAUGUUUGUUUAUUUCAGCUUUGUGUACAGUCAUUAAAAGUGCCUUGUUUCAUUUUUAUAGGAUGAAGUUAUUUAUUUUCUAUUUUCACUGUUUUGCAUAUUGCUGUUAAUAAGCAUUGUAAUCAUGCUGGCAUUUUGCAAUCCCAGUCGGUAUGCUUUCUAAAAACUGAGGGAAACUUACUGGGGAAAUAGAAUAACAAUCUCCAUUUUUUUCUUUACUAUCUAAAAGUUUAUCGGUAUCUUGAUGUAUAUAUAUAUUAAGGUGUGGCUGUUUAAAAUUCUAAUGACAUAUAUCAACACAUUCAAUGGCUGUUGUUAACCUUUGAAGUAAAAAGGAGAUCACUUUUUACCAAAUAACCAAAAAUUUUUAGUCUGUCAAAGUGCACAGGUAUGUUCUCAGAACAUUUUUCACAAUGUGUAUCAGAAAUAUGUUUGCUAUCCUUAGAGACAGAAAUGAAUAUAAUAAAUUGAUCUGCUUAUUUAUUAAAAUUAUUAUUCUAGACUUACAAAAGGCUUAAAAAGAACAAUCAUUUAAUCAGUACCAUUCUGUAUCUUAUAUAACAGAUCUUUGCCAAAUUCUAGAUAUUAUAGUGUUGCCUGUCUGUUCUAAAGCGAACCAGCCACUUUUUCAAUCUGGCUUUUUGGAAGAUUGUAUUUAAAGUUCUUCAAGGAUGAAGAAAAAAAUCUGUUAAUUAGGUAAACCACUAUUAUUUAUAUUUAUAAUUUACUUUUUUUUACUUUUAUAAUGCAUUUUACUCCCAGUAUUAUGUUCAUUUAAUAAAUUAUUUUUUCACUACAA